GCUGUUUCCAGCGAGUCAGAUUCCAGAUCGCGCUCCAGCCUGGACUCGGAAUUCCUGCCCCGCGGGUCUGCAUUUUCACAGCGGCAGGUGUGAGUGCCGCGCAGCUGGAGACCAGAAGCCUGAGGCAGCUCGGCCCUCCCCAGCCCAAAGUGCCGUUAUUCCGUUUCUGUAUCAGUAAACACGUUUCAUUUUCCGUAGACCAGGGAAGGGUGAUGGGUGAUCCCAGUCCUCGCAGUGAAUUCCGGGCCACAAAAUUCAAAACGCUUGCGGGCAAAGCCGUGCGCGGUGGCUCAAGCCUGUAAUUCCAGCACUUUGGGAGGCCGAGGCGGGCGGAUCACCUGAGGUCGGGAUUUCCAGACCAGCCUGACCAACAUAGAGAAACCCCGCCUCUACUAAAAAUACAAAAUUAGCCGGGGGUGGCGCAUGCCUGUAAUCCCAGCUAGUCGGGAGGCUGAGGCAGGAGACUCACUUGAACCCGGGAGGCGGAGGUUGCUGUGAGCCGAGAUCGCGCCACUGCACUCCAGCCUGGGCAACAAGAGCGAAACUCCGUUUCAAAAAAAAACAAAAAACAAAAAGCUUUCGGGCGCCGAGGGCAGCCCCGCCCUGAAUUUUGUGAGCGACCGCGCUGGGCCGUUUCUCUUUCUUUUCCGGACCCUGCAGUGGCGCCUAAAGUCUGCGAGGAGGAAGUCGCCUCUGUGCUCAGCCCCACAGUCUUCGUUACAACCUCAUGGUGCUGUCCCAGGAUGGAUCUGUGCAGUCAGGGUUUCUCGCUGAGGGACAUCUGGAUGGUCAGCCCUUCCUGCGCUAUGACAGGCAGAAACGCAGGGCAAAGCCCCAGGGACAGUGGGCAGAAAAUGUCCUGGGAGCUAAGACCUGGGACACAGAGACCGAGGACUUGACAGAGAAUGGGCAAGACCUCAGGAGGACCCUGACUCAUAUCAAGGACCAGAAAGGAGGCUUGCAUUCCCUCCAGGAGAUUAGGGUCUGUGAGAUCCAUGAAGACAGCAGCACCAGGGGCUCCCGGCAUUUCUACUACGAUGGGGAGCUCUUCCUCUCCCAAAACCUGGAGACUCAAGAAUCGACAGUGCCCCAGUCCUCCAGAGCUCAGACCUUGGCUAUGAACGUCACAAAUUUCUGGAAGGAAGAUGCCAUGAAGACCAAGACACACUAUCGCGCUAUGCAGGCAGACUGCCUGCAGAAACUACAGCGAUAUCUGAAAUCCGGGGUGGCCAUCAGGAGAACAGUGCCCCCCAUGGUGAAUGUCACCUGCAGCGAGGUCUCAGAGGGCAACAUCACCGUGACAUGCAGGGCUUCCAGCUUCUAUCCCCGGAAUAUCACACUGACCUGGCGUCAGGAUGGGGUAUCUUUGAGCCACAACACCCAGCAGUGGGGGGAUGUCCUGCCUGAUGGGAAUGGAACCUACCAGACCUGGGUGGCCACCAGGAUUCGCCAAGGAGAGGAGCAGAGGUUCACCUGCUACAUGGAACACAGCGGGAAUCACGGCACUCACCCUGUGCCCUCUGGGAAGGCGCUGGUGCUUCAGAGUCAACGGACAGACUUUCCAUAUGUUUCUGCUGCUAUGCCAUGUUUUGUUAUUAUUAUUAUUCUCUGUGUCCCUUGUUGCAAGAAGAAAACAUCAGCGGCAGAGGGUCCAGAGCUUGUGAGCCUGCAGGUCCUGGAUCAACACCCAGUUGGGACAGGAGACCACAGGGAUGCAGCACAGCUGGGAUUUCAGCCUCUGAUGUCAGCUACUGGGUCCACUGGUUCCACUGAGGGCACCUAGACUCUACAGCCAGGCGGCCAGGAUUCAACUCCCUGCCUGGAUCUCACCAGCACUUUCCCUCUGUUUCCUGACCUAUGAAACAGAGAAAAUAACAUCACUUAUUUAUUGUUGUUGGAUGCUGCAAAGUGUUAGUAGGUAUGAGGUGUUUGCUGCUCUGCCACGUAGAGAGCCAGCAAAGGGAUCAUGACCAACUCAACAUUCCAUUGGAGGCUAUAUGAUCAAACAGCAAAUUGUUUAUCAUGAAUGCAGGAUGUGGGCAAACUCACGACUGCUCCUGCCAACAGAAGGUUUGCUGAGGGCAUUCACUCCAUGGUGCUCAUUGGAGUUAUCUACUGGGUCAUCUAGAGCCUAUUGUUUGAGGAAUGCAGUCUUACAAGCCUACUCUGGACCCAGCAGCUGACUCCUUCUUCCACCCCUCUUCUUGCUAUCUCCUAUACCAAUAAAUACGAAGGGCUGUGGAAGAUCAGAGCCCUUGUUCACGAGAAGCAAGAAGCCCCCUGACCCCUUGUUCCAAAUAUACUCUUUUGUCUUUCUCUUUAUUCCCACGUUCGCCCUUUGUUCAGUCCAAUACAGGGUUGUGGGGCCCUUAACAGUGCCAUAUUAAUUGGUAUCAUUAUUUCUGUUGUUUUUGUUUUUGUUUUUGUUUUUGUUUUUGAGACAGAGUCUCACUCUGUCACCCAGGCUGCAGUUCACUGGUGUGAUCUCAGCUCACUGCAACCUCUGCCUCCCAGGUUCAAGCACUUCUCGUACCUCAGACUCCCGAAUAGCUGGGAUUACAGACAGGCACCACCACACCCAGCUAAUUUUUGUAUUUUUUGUAGAGACGGGGUUUCGCCAAGUUGACCAGCCCAGUUUCAAACUCCUGACCUCAGGUGAUCUGCCUGCCUUGGCAUCCCAAAGUGCUGGGAUUACAAGAAUGAGCCACCGUGCCUGGCCUAUUUUAUUAUAUUGUAAUAUAUUUUAUUAUAUUAGCCACCAUGCCUGUCCUAUUUUCUUAUGUUUUAAUAUAUUUUAAUAUAUUACAUGUGCAGUAAUUAGAUUAUCAUGGGUGAACUUUAUGAGUGAGUAUCUUGGUGAUGACUCCUCCUGACCAGCCCAGGACCAGCUUUCUUGUCACCUUGAGGUCCCCUCGCCCCGUCACACCGUUAUGCAUUACUCUGUGUCUACUAUUAUGUGUGCAUAAUUUAUACCGUAAAUGUUUACUCUUUAAAUAGA